GCCGCCGCCGCCAUCUUGCGGUCCCGCGGGGGCGCCUCCUGGGCGUCCGGUCCCGCCCGCGCCGCGGUCCGCCUGGGCCCGCGUCCUUGGCCCCAGAGGCCGACGGCGUGCUUCGGCGGGGCGUGGGCGGCUGGGCACCCGAGGGCGUGCGCUCUGGGCUGCGGCGGGGAGUGGGCUCUGGAGGUGGCGCAAGCUGCGUCUGUCGCCCGCUCCCGGCUGUCAGCGGCGCGGGGAGGCUAGGGCACGGCGCGGGACCCCUUGGGAGUGAGAGCCGCCCCCCGACCCCUGCCCCGGCCCGGGGAGAGCUCGCUGCAGCCGGCCCUCGGGUUCCGCGGAGGGCGUCGCUUGUCACCUUUCCGCCAGGUUUAGAACUCGGCCGUCAGGUGUAGGACGCGCCGGGGAGGUGGAGAGUCCUUGGAGGUGCCUGGCGAGGGCUGCCCGGUGCUGUUGGCACGGACCCAGGUACGUGUUUAUGUAAAGGUGAUGGAUGAGUAUUUAUACGACCAGAACAAUACUACACUGUAUGAAAAUGGUGUAAAAGAAGUAAAAGACAUGGUCCCUUCCGGUUGGUAACUUUUUCAUACUGUAAUUUUAGGCUCCCAGAAUGGGAAUACUGGUUUAUAAAAAAUGAUUACAUGACCAUAUUAAGUGGAUUUUGGAGAGUUUUCAUGAUACAUUCUGAAACUGUUGAUUGUAUAGUAUGGAUAAACUGAUUGUAUAAUAUGAUUGUAUAAUAUGUUUGUAUAAUUGUAUAAUAUGAUUGUAUAAUAUGGACAGUGAGGCAAUUUCAGUAAUUAAAGCCCUUAGAGGCUUAAAUAAAAUAGUGCAGUCUUGCUUUUCCAUUAAUCUCAGGAUCCAUACUUUUAUGAUGUUAGUGAAAUCUUAUGAAGAGAUAUGUUUUAGUGCUUCAAUGACUAAGUUUUUAAAAAUAGAACUAAGACUCAUUUUUUUUCCCAGAAAGUAUUACUCUAUUUGUACAAAAAUAUUUAUACAAAAAUAUUUCUUCAGUACCUACUACACCAGGCAUUGUGUUAGUUGCUGGGGAUACAGCAGCUAACGAAACAAAGACCUAUUCAUGGAGCUUACAUCAAGUCUGAUAUUUAAAUGUGUUUGAAAAAAACAUACAGUAAGGGUAAAUUCAAGUGACAUCAUUUAAAAAAUUUGUAAUAAGAAUGUUUUAGGGCUUUCUUGGAUGUAAAAAUGUAAAAUAUUUUUUGAGUGCUUGAUACUUAUUUCAGGAAGUGUUCAGUGUUGACCUGUGUGACCAAGAGAAAUACAAUAUCAAUUUAAAAAUCUUUUUCAUAUAUUGCUAAUUUGACUGCACUUUCAUGCUUUAUUGUGGCAGAAGUCUACCUGGAAUACUUAUGAAUUAGAAAAUAAAUACCGUUUGGUUAUACGUACAAAAUUUAUGAGAGUUCAGGCCCUAGAGUCAGACCUGGUUUGACUUCCCACUUUCAUUGCUUUGAGUUAUAUGACCUUGGACUACUGUUUACCUUCUAAGUUGAAUCAUUUGUAAACUUGGUAUAUUAAAAUGUAAUGAAAGUAUCUACUUCAUGGACUUGUGAGGGUUAAAUAACAUAGUUCAUACAAAGUUAUUGAUACAUGAGUGCCCAAUAAACGCUAGCUGUUCCGUUAGUAGAUAUUCUGUGUACUAUAUAGUAUUAAUAUAUGUUUUGUAUAUAUGAUUACCUUAACAUGAUGCCACAGAUACUCAGCAGCAUAACCCUUGUGUAACUGGGAAACAGUUUAAUCAGUGAUACAACUUAAUUAGCUAAAACCUGUUAGAAACAUUGAAGGUAGUCAUCACCUGCAUUGCUGUGGCUACAUUGUUUGUGUAUUUGAGCAGAGCACCCAGCCUUCCUCAUUAGUCUGCACUGCAUAGCUAAGAAUUUACAAAGACCUUGUCAAGAACUGUGAAGGGACUGAAAAUUUAGCCUGCUGCAGUUUUGUAGAUGUUGGUAGAAGACAUGAGAUUUCCUGAGUUAGACAGUGGACAUCAUUGUUCAUGGCACUGCAAGUGGAAUGGGCUUUAUAUUUGUGUUGUUUUCCUUGCCCUCCUCAAGUUCCAUGGAGGUGACAGAGGUGUUCGGGUAGAUGCUACUCACAUAGUGAGUUUGCAUCAUAACUAGAAACCCUGAGCUUAGAGAACCGGAAUCUUUCAUAGUGGGCUGCACAGAAACCUACCUGACCUUUGUUCCAGUAGAAGACCUUAUCUUGAUUAUAUUGGUCAGUGAACAAACCUGCCCCUCUCCUCAGAAGGGAGGUGUUGUCUUCUAAGACAGUUCACUAUUUAAUACAUUCUUGAAAAGAUAGCCUGGGUAAAAACCCCCAGGACUACUUCUUGCAAGAUGUGCAGAAAUGCUAGAGGCCCAUGGAGAAUUGUCUCCUAAACACACCUCUGAGUAACUAGCCUAAAUGGGGGUCACAGAGUUCAUAAAUUAAUGUUCAUGUGCAUUGUCUGUUUAUUCUUAAGUUACAUUUUAGAAGUGUUUUCUGUUUUCUGAAAUGCUCUGUGUGAUAUACUACUGCUUAUCCCAUAUUAAAAUUUUAUUCUCUUAACAGAAAACAAAUACUAAAGUUGAUAUGCAUACUGAGAUGUUCAGGAGUGACUAUAUUGGUGUCUUCAGCUUAGUUUGAUGUGCAUCAAAAAUUAAGUGGAUGUCUGGACAGGGCAGAUAGAUAUGCUGCAAAGUAAAUACAGCAAAAUGUUCAUCGUAGAAUGCCCCUUCACAGAUGUAGUCACUACAAAUCUUAAAUUGCGAAAUCCAUCGGAUAGAAAAGUGUGUUUCAAAGUGAAGACUACAGCACCUCGCCGGUACUGUGUGAGGCCCAACAGUGGAAUUAUUGACCCAGGGUCAACUGUGACUGUUUCAGUAAUGCUACAGCCCUUUGACUAUGAUCCGAAUGAAAAGAGUAAACACAAGUUUAUGGUACAGACAAUUUUUGCUCCACCAAACACUUCAGAUAUGGAAGCUGUGUGGAAAGAGGCAAAACCUGAUGAAUUAAUGGAUUCCAAAUUGAGAUGCGUAUUUGAAAUGCCCAAUGAAAAUGAUAAAUUGGGUAUAACUCCACCAGGGAAUGCUCCGACUGUCACUUCAAUGAGCAGCAUCAACAACACAGUUGCAACACCUGCCAGUUAUCACACGAAGGAUGACCCCAGGGGACUCAGUGUGUUGAAACAGGAGAAACAGAAGAAUGAUAUGGAACCUAGCAAAGCUGUUCCACUGAAUGCAUCUAAGCAAGAUGGACCUAUGCCAAAACCACACAGUGUUUCACUUAAUGAUACCGAAACAAGGAAACUAAUGGAAGAGUGUAAAAGACUUCAGGGAGAAAUGAUGAAGCUAUCAGAAGAAAAUCGGCACCUGAGAGAUGAAGGUUUAAGGCUCAGAAAGGUAGCACAUUCGGAUAAACCUGGAUCAACCUCAACUGCAUCCUUCAGAGAUAAUGUCACCAGUCCUCUUCCUUCACUUCUUGUUGUAAUUGCAGCCAUUUUCAUUGGAUUCUUUCUAGGGAAAUUCAUCUUGUAGAGUGAAGCAUGCAGAGUGCUGUUUCUUUUUUUUUUUUUCUCUUGACCAGAAAAAGAUUUGUUUACCUACCAUUUCAUUGGUAGUAUGGCCCACGGUGACCAUUUUUUUGUGUGUACAGCGUCAUAUAGGCUUUGCCUUUAAUGAUCUCUUACGGUUAGAAAACACAAUAAAAACAAACUGUUCGGCUACUGGACAGGUUGUAUAUUACCAGAUCAUCACUAGCAGAUGUCAGUUGCACAUUGAGUCCUUUAUGAAAUUCAUAAAUAAAGAAUUGUUCUUUCUUUGUGGUUUUAAUAAGAGUUCAAGAAUUGUUCAGAGUCUUGUAAAUGUUAUUUUAAUAAUCCCUUUAAAUUUUAUCUGUUGCUGUUACCUCUUGAAAUAUGAUUUAUUUAGAUUGCUAAUCCCACUCAUUCAGGAAAUGCCAAGAGGUAUUCCUUGGGGAAAUGGUGCCUCUUACAGUGUAAAUUUUUCCUCCUUUACCUUUGCUAAUAUCAUGGCAGAAUUUUUCUUAUCCCUUGUGAGGCAGUUGUUGACUGAGUUUUUCAUCCUUACAAUCCUGUCCCAUGGUAUUUAACAUAAAAAAAAAUAAAACUGUUAACAGAUUCUUGCUCGAUAGCUUGUUUGUGUCUGUCGUGUUAUUAGAGGGAACUCCACUAUAUAUGGUCACUUGAAAUUAUGAUGCAAAGGUUUCUCUUGCAUUGAAACCCUCUUGGAUAUUACAGUAUUUUUAAUUGAAAGUCCUAAUUCUGUUAAGGAAAGGAGUUGAUUAAAUUUUAAGGUACCACUGGUAUUUUGGGAGAUUAUAAUCAGUUUGUUUUCAAGAUAAUAGAAAAUAAGGUCCAUGAGAAUAGAAGUUAUGUGAUUUCAGUGAGUUGAUGUGUACAGCAUGGCUGUGCUCCAUCUGAUUUACCCCAUUCUUAAGUUCUGAGAGUAUGUUCUCAAGGAAGAUUUAACUCUCUUUGGUUUUAAAUUACUUUUUAACCAGCCUAAUAAAUAAGUCUUACUACUUUUCAUAAUAUUUCAUAAUAGUUAAAAGUAGGUGUUUUUUUCGUGCUCAAUUUGGCACUCAAAAUAAUGUUCAUUAUGGAAGUUUGGUAAUACUGAGCAAGCCUGUGGAAUUUUCUUUAUGAAAAAUGAUUUUAGCCUUUGCAAAUGUUAACCAUGUGAAACACAUUUUCAGUAUAAGUAUGCGUUACAGGGUUUGAUACUUUCCUGCACUUAGGUUUGUCCUAUUCUUCAUUUAUUCAUACUAGGAUAGAAAAUUUUGGAAUCAGAAAAUAGAUCCAGUGUUUAGCUACAUACAAUCUAGUACAAGUGAAUUUUUAUUCUUAAACAUAGGUGUGUUGGCUCUUUUUUUAAAAGAUGCGCUCUACCUGAAAAGGAAAUUGGAUUUUAGAACUGGAUGUGGUGCAGUGAAGUAUUUUAGGCCCAGGUCUGUGUACACAUUUUAUAGAAGAAUGAAGUACUCUGAAGUAUUUUGGUUGCCUUUUCAUUUCAACUGUGUUUUGAAUUUGUCAGAUCACACAUAUAUUGUGUUAUUGGGCGCUGUGGUAUCUUUUAUAAAACCUCUUGCUUGUGUGCAAAAGUUCCUAAAAGGAAACACAAGUAAUGCCUAUCCAUUACUAGCAUGCUAUGCUGCAUGCUUUACUGCCAUUGCUGUAUGCUUUACUGUCUUUGUAAAAAUCCCCCUCUCCCCUUUUCUGGUAACUGGAAAAGCAUGCUAAAAAUAGUCUUAUAUUUUCACCCCAUAAAUGCAGAAUCAGUAAUUCCUUGGCUUAAAGCUCUUAUAUAAUCAAUAUUAUUGGUGGUAAAUACCAAGUUUGGUAUCUCAUAGCUAUCUUUUUUUAAAGAAAUUAAGUUCUUGAAAAUUUAGCCAAAUCCCGUUUUAUGGGAAUGCUCUUUAGAAUUCAUUUUGUUCAGCCCCUUUGUUCUAUGGUUGAGAAAUCUGAGGCCUUACGAAGGUUAAGAGAACUUUCCCCGUGUCUCACAGGUAGGUAGAGGCAGAGCUGGAACUAGAUAUCUGGUCUGUUGACUCUAGCUCAGUGUCUUCUGGUAACUGUUGAAAAUUGUCUUAGUUUGAGAGAUGGCUGAAAUAAUGAACAUAAAAUGCUAUUUAUAAUAACAAGUAUAUGUGAAAUUUCUUAUUGUAAGACUACUACCGGCUUACUGUUGAAUAGUUUGGUUAUAGUGUUUAGGCUAGAAAUGCCUCCCACAUUGGUAAUAAACAUUACAAAAUACAAUGUAUUUUUAGGUAGGCAUUUUAUAAAAUGCAUUAUGCCAUGGUUGCUUUUGAGAUAGAUUGUAGUCUGGGUAGCAUCUUUAAAAUGUAUGUGGGCUUAACUGUUGUUCAUAUCAGGAGAUGCUCUGAUUGUAUAGGUGAGACUCUGUUUCUGUUAUUUUUAAUUGCUGUAUGAAAUGUGAUCAGAUUAUUUUACUACCAACAGUUAUAGUUUGAAAGUCCAACUGUAUUAAUUGACUGAUAAUAUGAUAAUAUAGAGAUUAAAUUGUUUGUCUUCAUUCCUUAUAUGUUUAGAAGUUUUUGCUUUGUCUGCCUGCUUACUUGUAUAUGUAAGCAUGAGGGAAAUACACUGUUGCUAAUACUGAAAUUACAAUCAAGUAACUAAGGCCUUGAGUUCAUAUGUGACACUGAAUGCACUAGCUUCCUUCGUUCUAUAACUAAUGUACCUUAACUUCCCCCAUUCUUAUAUUUACAAGAAGCUAAGUCAUUAUGUUCUGAGUGUGUGGUAUGUUCCCUUAAAAAAAAAUGACACUUGGAAGAAAAAUGUAUGAAAUUCAGAAAUUCCGAUCAAAGAAAAGUAAUUCUUUCUUUUUUUUUUUGAGACAGAGUCUUGCUUUGUUGCCCAGGCUGGAGGGCAGUGGUGUGAUCUCACCUCACUGCAGCUUCCGCCUCCUGGGUUCAAGUGAUUCUCAUGGCUCAGCCGCCUGAGUAGCUGGGAUUACAGGUGUGAGCCAACAAGCCCGGCUAAUUUUUGUAUUUUUAGUAGAGACAAGGUUUCACCAUGUUGGUCAGGCUGGGCUCAAACUCCUGAAUCCGCCUGCCUCGGCCUCCCAAAGUGCUGGGAUUACAGGUGUGAGCUGCCGCACCCAGCCAAGAAAAAUAAUACUCUUAAAUACUUAGAUGUUCACCUAAAGUUGAUAUUAUUUGGUAUGGGAAUUACUUUUGAACUGUAAUCUUUCAGAUUACACCACUUUGAAAACAAGUUUUAACAGUAGGGUAAAAAUAUAGUUUUUGAGGGUAUUCCCAACUUGUGAUCUUCUACCACUUUAGAGACAUUCAAGUAAUAGUUUUCUUAGAGCUUUGCACAUUCCUAUUCACUGAGAUUUUAAAAAUUUCACCUUUAUUCGAGGGAAGGAUCAAUGCUUAUUACCAUUUGGAAAAACGAAGAUCAGAAGGUAAAUGAUCUUUAUUUUCUAGCUUUAAAGGGAAAUUAAACCAUUCAUGAAUAAACUUUAAAAAUGUGAAGUGUCCUUUUCCUUUUCACAAUACAAAAAAAAUUUCAACAGAUUGUGUGGUUUGUGCAUUUAUAUCCUGUUAAGCAUUAAUAGCUAAUCACUGGGACUUGAAUUCUGAUGGCAGAUAGUCUCUUGCUUAGUGAGAUGGAGUUAACUAUUUUUUAGUAGGAAGUGAGAACAGCUGAUUUUCAUGCCACGUUUCAUAGCCCCACUUUUGGUAGACUACCACCACGCUUCUUCGCGUAAGCAGUGGCAUCUUGGGAAUGAAUGCCCAGCCGCUCGUGGGUUGGUGCAAAGAAGUAUAAACAUAUAUCACUAAGGAAAAAGAAAGUUUGUCUUGCCCUUCUGACACAGUGUGUGCACUUCAGGCAAUUUUUGGAAAAUAUAAAAAAUUCCAAAUUCUGCCUUUCAGCAGCAUCAAUUGCUAGGAACAUUUCAUUCAUUUCCCUGUAAUAUUAAUGUUCUUUAAGCAUAAUCACUAAUUAUAAGUUGUAUCCUAUUUUUUUCCAGCUUAAUUUCUGUGGUUUAUUGAAAACCAAGUAUAAAUGUGACUAAAAGCAUUUUGCUUUGUUUUUAUAGUUAACUUUCUUAAGGUUAUGGACAUUUUAUAAUGUAACAUUUGAUUGGCCUGGCCUCUUGACAAUUCCCUUCUAGUUAUGCAUAUCCUCCUGUUGCCACAUUUCUUGUUUUAAAACUCAGUUUCUUGUUUUCCAGUUGUUGCUAUGUAUAACACCCAUCUUGAAAGAGAGUAUAUAGGAAGUUAUUCAGAUAACUUUUGUAGUAGUGAUAUUCAACUAUAGCAGUACCUUAACUCAUGAUGAGCUUAGGAACAUAAAAGAUAAUUGUUGCUUGAAUAGCACCCCCAGAGAUACUGACCUAAUUGGUCUGGGGUGGAGAUCUGGCAUGGUAGUUUUUUUCAAGCUCCAAUCAUCGGCCAGACAGUUGCUUUAUGUAGGUUUUUAAAUGCCAAAGGCAGAUAUGAAGUAGAUUUAAUUAAGACUUGACUUCAGCAAUACAGGGGAACUUAAAAUACUUAUUUUUCUUUAAACUGCAGGAGUCACUGUUAGGUAUUGCUUAAAAAAAAUUGCAUAAAAGCUUUGCUUGUCAAGUUAGGAUUGCUGGAAUACCACUAAAGAUUUUUGACUUGUGAAUAAAUGAGCUGUCAUCGCAAAAAGGCGAUUUGAGAAAUGUGGGCUUCAGUAUUAAUUGCCAUUUUGCUGACACCCAGUGUACCUACCUACCUGAGAAAUUUAUUUUGUCCAUCAUGUAUUUCUCAAAGCAAAAGGUGGUUUUCAAGUAUAAUGUCGUUUUCAACAUGCUUAUUACUUAGUUUUACGUCAGCUCAUUUCAUCAUCAUUGAUAACUUGUGAAAUACUUAUCUCCAUCCUAUGGAAUAGGGGAGACGGGUUUAGACAGGUUCAAUUAGCUCAAGUCUACACAGCUGAAGUAGCAGAGAAAGUGGGAUCUAGAUGGUCUGAUCCUAGUGAUCUACCAUAUGAAGGACAUAGUUUGUGUCCUGGUCCAAGUCAAAUAUUGACUCCUCACAAACAGUAAGUAUGGCAAUUUUGUGAUGCCUUUGAUUCCACUUUACAUGGAGUACUAUUAUUUGUGAAAUGUCUUUAAGAUUUUUGGUCUUAAAUUUUUGAAGACUGCUUUCCCCCUUUAUCUCCCAGAAAAUUGAGAAGAAGUAAACUCCUGCCCACUAACAAUCUCAGUCCGUGAACAAAACCAACAUGAACAUUCCUAAACAAGAGUGUGUGUUACUCUAAGAAGAAGGCUAUAGAAUUUAUGGAAAUGGCUUAUGUAACCUACAAGACUGGAGAACAGAAUGUGACUGGCCUUUUCUAAUGGUCCUUUAAGAUUUAAUGAUUAAAGCAAGAGUUUUUUAUAAUUGACUUUGUGGUCUAAAUUCUUGAUACUGUUUAUAAUUCUACAAAGAACAAAAAUUGUUAUGUACUAUAGGCACUUAAGAACCCUGAGGAAAAAUAAUACAAUGUGUGUGUGUGAGAGAGAGAGUGAGUUACUGACAUUGUUCCAAAAAAAAAAAAAAAAAAAAAAAAAAUGUGGAGGGUUGAAAUGGUAAGGAAUUGGAAUCUUUUGUAUUUUCGAGCAAUAAGAAUUCCUAUUCUUGUUUCAAAUAGAGGUUUGUUAGGAAUUACAGUUGUGGGGAGCAAACUUUCUUUUUUGUGCUGUUUUAAUUCAAAAUGUAUAUCCUUAAUUGUAUAUAAUAUGUAGAUAAAUAUAUGAGGGUAUUAAGCUACUUUGAAUUAAAUUUAAGGAUAUAUUUCACAUGAAAACAAAUACAAACGAGAAUCAAAAUAAAGUUUUGCAAAGUA